AGUUCUUUUCUCACCUUGACUGCAAGAUGAAACUCCUUGUGCUAGCUGUGCUGCUCACAGUGGCCGCCGCCGACAGCGGCAUCAGCCCUCGGGCCGUGUGGCAGUUCCGCAAAAUGAUCAAGUGCGUGAUCCCGGGGAGUGACCCCUUCUUGGAAUACAACAACUACGGCUGCUACUGUGGCUUGGGGGGCUCAGGCACCCCCGUGGAUGAACUGGACAAGUGCUGCCAGACACAUGACAACUGCUAUGACCAGGCCAAGAAGCUGGACAGCUGUAAAUUUCUGCUGGACAACCCGUACACCCACACCUAUUCAUACUCGUGCUCUGGCUCGGCAAUCACCUGUAGCAGCAAAAACAAAGAGUGUGAGGCCUUCAUUUGCAACUGCGACCGCAACGCUGCCAUCUGCUUUUCAAAAGCUCCAUAUAACAAGGCACACAAGAACCUGGACACCAAGAAGUAUUGUCAGAGUUGAAUAUCACCUCUCAAAAGCAUCACCUCUAUCUGCCUCAUCUCACACUGUACUCUCCAAUAAAGCACCUUGUUGAAAGAC